CUCUCGCUUCCUCUCCCGUGUCUGGGUCUCACUCUGCCGGGUGUGCAGAUAAGACCUGGGCUGCCUGUCCAAAGGGUCGUGGUUAAUGACUGAUCCUGGAGCUGCAGGGCUCCUGGCUCCCCGUCCAGGACUACGGCUACCUCCAAGUUCCAUCUCCUUUCUCUCUAUAUAGUCUAUUAAUGGUAUUUAAAGCAUGUGAUGAAGAUCACAAAGGAUAUCUCAGCAGAGAGGACUUUAAAACUGCUGUUGUAAUGCUGUUUGGGUACAAGCCCUCCAAGAUAGAAGUGGAUUCUGUGAUGUCUUCAAUAAAUCCAAAUACUUCUGGUAUAUUACUCGAGGGGUUUUUAAAUAUUGUCAGGAAAAAGAAGGAAGCUCAACGAUAUCGGAACGAAGUAAGACACAUCUUCACAGCCUUUGACACCUACUAUCGUGGAUUUUUAACUUUGGAAGAUUUCAAAAAAGCAUUUAGGCAGGUGGCUCCCAAAUUACCGGAAAGGACUGUUCUUGAGGUAUUCAGGGAAGUAGAUCGAGAUUCAGAUGGUCACGUCAGCUUUAGAGACUUUGAAUAUGCCCUGAACUAUGGACAGAAGGAAGCCUAACUAUUGUGAACUACUUUUGGUAACUCUGGGGAGAUCAAUAGAUUGUAAUGUCAGCAGACUCGACUCUACUAAUGAUGUCAUGCUACAGACUUGUGAUUAAACAUUUAAAAAUUUUUAAUUUUUGUGGGUACAUAGUAGGUGCAUAUGUAUACAUACACACACAUAUAUGGGUUACGGGAGAUAUUUUGGCACAGGCAUGCAAUAAGUAAUUGACUAAAUUUUUAAUCAUAAUUUUUGGAUGCUGAUGAUAGACUUGCAUCUCAGAAUCCUAGAGAUGGUUGCUGCCGGGGGUCUCCUUCUGUGUGGCCAGCAGCCCUGAGUCAGGCCGCCAUUGCUAGAGCUGGGGCUAGGGAUGGCACUGGUGGUCCUCCUCCUCCUCACUCUUCUUGCCCCCUACCCUCUCCACACUGCAGGCCACGGUGCUCUACUCACUCACUUCAUUGUCCUCACCAUCCCACCCUGAAUCUCAUCAUCUCCUAAUAUCUGCAGAGGGGCAGACUUUUCCUGCCAAUGGUGCCAGUUUCCUUCAUUUGCUCAACAUUGGUUGAACAAAUAAUAGCACCUACACAUACAGAAUACUUACUAUGUUCCAAGCAAUCAGCCAGGCCUUGGGAAGCAUAGGCUUAAGACUUCUCUAAGAUAGGCUCAUGCCUACAAUCCCAGCACUUUGGGAGGCCAAAGCAGGAGGAUCACUUGAGCCUAGGAAUUGGAGACUAGCCUGGGCAACAUACCGAGACCCCAUCCCUACCAAAAAAUUAAUAAUAAAAAAUUAUCUGGAUUUAGUGGUGUGUACCUGUAGUCCCAGCUACUUGGGAGGCUGAGGUGGAAGGAUCAUUUGAGCCCAGGGGUUUGAAGCUUCAGUGAGCCAUGAUUGCACUGUCGCACUCCAGCCUGGAUGAUAGAGCAAGACCCUGUCUCUAAAAAAACACUUUCAAUUAAAAAAAAACAUAUAAAGACUUCUCUAAGAUAAUGUCCCUGAGUCCAAAUCAUCACUGUAAAGUGGUCCCAGGGCACUGUCUGUGCAAGACAAAGAAAUCGGCUUGGGCUAACAUGAGCAAGCCCUCUCGGGCUAUAUACAGAGGAAGAACAGGGUGAUGAGGGUACUGGGGGCAAGAGACAUGUUUGCAGAACCCUUUAGGAUGGUCUAGGCUUGGGAGUCUCACUGUGGAGAAGCAAGCCUUGAGCUGCUCAGCUGCCCUCUGCUCCAUACCCCCUGGUUUCUAGCAGUCACGUCCUGCACCCAGACACUUAGCCAUGUGUGUUCACGUUCCCCAUGCCUUGCCUGUCCUGCUGGGCUCCAGUAACUGCUAUACUGGAGCAAGAACAGCAAUGCUGGACACUCAGCAUUUAGUGAAGGUAAUUCCAAAAUACUGGUAUCAGUACUCUUAUUUAUAAGUGUACGGAAUGCAUAACAUGAACAUUAGUCAAAGAACUUUUAAUAUAAUUCACUUUUUAAGUGUUAAAAUUUAAAGGUCAAGUAAAAUUGUAAAUUUGUAAUAUGGAAACAUUAAGCGUCAUUAUCAUACAAAUUAUUAGCAGAUAACCUUAAUAAAAAUAAACGUUUGCGGGUUUUUUUUGAGACAGAGUCUCACUUUGUCACCUAAGCUGGAGUACAGUGCGCGAUCUCGGCUCACUGCAACUUCCGCCUCCUGGGAUCAAGUGAUUCUCCUGCCUUAGCCUCCUGAGUAUCUGGGUUUACAGGUGUGUACCGCCACACCCGGCUAAUUUUUAGUAGAGAAGGGGUUUCACCAUGUUGGCCAGGCUGGUCUUGAACUCCUGACCUCAAGUGAUCCGUCUGCCUCGGCCUCCCAAAGUGCUGGGAUUACAGGCGUGAGCCACCAUGCCUGGCCAAUAAAAAUAAAGUUUUAAACUGUCAAAUAAGAGGAGCCUAACAAGAUGUGACAACUAAAUGUCAUUUGGUAUCCUGGAUGAGAUCACGGAAUAAAAAAUAAACAUUGGCCGGACACAGUGACUCAGCCUGUAAUCCCAGCACUUCGGGAGGCCGAGGCGGGUGGAUCACGAGGUCGGGAGAUCGAGACCAUCCUGGCUAACACGGUGAAACCCCGUCUCUACUAAAAAUACAAAAAACAAAAAAAGAUUAGCUGGGCGUGGUGGCAGGUGCCUGUAGUCCCAGCUGCUCGGGAGGCUGAGGCAGGAGAAUAGCAUGAACCUGGGAGGCAGAGCUUGCAGUGAGCUGAAAUGGUGCCACUGCACUCCAGUCUGGGCAACAGAGCGAGACUCCCUCUCAAAAAAAAAAAAAAAAAAAAAAAAAAAGACAUUAAGUAGAAACAAAUCAAGCAUGGACUUUAGCUAAUAAUAAUGUAUCACUAUUGGUUCAUUAAUUGUAACAAAUGUAUCCUACUCAUAUAUAAUGUUAAUAGUAGGGGAAACUGGGUGAGGUAUAUGGGAACCCUCUACUAUUUUCACAAUUUUUCUAUAAAUCUAAAACUAUUCUAAAAUUAAAAAUUCAUUUAAAAAAUAAAGUCUUAUUCAAAACCUGUUAAACUAAACUUUAUCUAAAAUGAAGAAAACAUUGAAAAUCAAGUAAAAAUAAAAUCUUAUUUCAAAUACAAA